ACAGUUAACACAACCUGGAGUAGCCCAUGCCAUACUGUGUCCUUUUAAGUCAGUAAAUUGAACUAAGUCGGUUAUUCGGCAAGCAGUUCCUAUAAAAAACUACAUGGCUAAGGUUCUUAAUGAUUGACCACAAGCAGAUCUUUCACCCUCGGAUCUCUAGCUACAAAAGGUGCAAUGGGACCUUUCUCUCUUCCCCAGCCCUUCCAUUCCUCCAGCCCCCCCAGGGUCCUAUACCCAGUUUGUGUGACUGUCCUUGAAGCUUUCCUGGAACCAUACUUAUCAUCAGACCUUUCCCAAAGUGACUCACUAACAUUGGUCUCUCUGAUGGUGUCUCUGGGAACCACUGGCUCAAUGACCUGUAAGGGCCGUUUCAGCACAUCCAUUCUGUCCAUCUCCAAGCCUUCACCGUAGGGAAGAACUUUUGCUCUCAGUCACCUCUCAGAGAGCUCUCUUUAUAGCUGAAGGUCCCUCUCAUGAGUUACAUCAAGAGUAACCUAGAAUUAUAUCAGCAAUACACAGCCAUGGCCCCCAAGCUACUGGCCCGCAUCUCCAAACUCCUCAUGAUCUGCCAGAAUGCAGGCAUUUCUGUACCAAAAGGCAUCAGAAACAUCUUUGAGUUCACUUGGGAAGAGCUCAUCAGUGACCCUUCAGUGCCUACCCCGUCCGACAUCUUGGGCCUGGAGGUCAGCUUUGGAGCCCCCCUGGUGGUGCUCAUGGAACCCACCUUUGUGCAGGUCCCCACACUGAAGAAGCCACUACCUCCACCACCACCAGCACCACCACGUCCAGUGCUGCUGGCAACCACUGGGGCAGCCAAGCGCUCCACCCUCUCUCCCACCAUGGCCCGUCAGGUGCGCACCCACCAGGAGACCCUGAACAGGUUUCAGCAGCAGUCCAUCCACCUGCUGACGGAGCUCCUCAGACUGAAGAUGAAGGCCAUGGUGGAGUCUAUGUCGGUGGGUGCCAACCCCUUGGACAUCACCAGGCGCUUUGUGGAGGCCAGCCAGCUCCUCCACCUCAAUGCCAAGGAGAUGGCCUUCAACUGCCUGAUCAGCACAGCCGGGAGAAGUGGCUACAGCAGCGGACAGUUGUGGAAAGAGUCCCUCGCAAACAUGUCCGCCAUUGGGGUGAACUCGCCUUACCAGCUGAUCUACCACUCUUCCACAGCCUGUCUGAGCUUUUCUCUCUCUGCUGGAAAAGAAGCCAAGAAGAAAAUAGGCAAAUCUAGAACUACAGAAGAUGUCAGCAUGCCGCCCCUGCAUCGAGGAGUGGGAACCCCUGCCAACAGCCUGGAGUUCAGCGACCCCUGCCCUGAGGCCCGGGAGAAGCUGCAGGAGUUGUGUCGCCACAUAGAAGCUGAAAGGGCCACAUGGAAAGGGAGGAAUAUCUCCUACCCCAUGAUCUUACGAAACUACAAGGCAAAGAUGCCCUCUCAUCUAAUGUUGGCCCGCAAAGGAGACUCUCAGACCCCGGGUUUACAUUACCCUCCCACUGCAGGUGCUCAGACUCUCAGCCCCACCUCUCACCCAUCUUCUGCCAACCAUCAUUUCAGUCAGCAUUGUCAAGAGGGGAAGGCACCCAAGAAGGCCUUCAAGUUUCAUUACACCUUCUAUGAUGGCUCCUCCUUCGUUUACUAUCCCUCUGGAAACGUCGCUGUAUGUCAGAUCCCCACAUGCUGCAGAGGGAGAACCAUCACCUGCCUCUUUAAUGACAUACCUGGAUUCUCCUUGCUGGCCCUAUUCAAUACUGAAGGCCAGGGCUGUGUUCACUACAACCUAAAAACCAGUUGCCCAUAUGUCUUAAUCUUGGAUGAGGAAGGUGGGACCACCAAUGACCAGCAGGGCUAUGUAGUCCACAAGUGGAGCUGGACUUCCAGGACAGAGACCCUGCUUUCCCUGGAAUACAAGGUGAAUGAGGAAAUGAAACUAAAGGUACUGGGACAGGACUCCAUCACAGUCACCUUCACCUCCCUGAAUGAGACAGUAACACUCACUGUGUCGGCCAACAAUUGUCCCCAUGGAAUGGCAUAUGACAAACGGCUGAACCGCAGAAUCAGCAACAUGGACGACAAGGUGUAUAAGAUGAGCCGAGCCCUGGCUGAGAUCAAGAAGCGGUUUCAGAAGACAGUGACUCAGUUCAUUAAUUCUAUCUUGCUGGCCGCAGGUCUGUUUACCAUUGAAUAUCCCACCAAAAAGGAGGAGGAAGAAUUUGUUCGGUUCAAGAUGAGAUCCAGAACUCAUCCCGAGCGGCUCCCCAAGCUAAGUUUAUACUCAGGAGAAAGUCUUUUACGAUCUCAGUCAGGCCACCUGGAAUCCUCAAUUGCAGAGACUUUGAAGGAUGAGCCUGAGUCUGCUCCUGUGAGCCCAGUUCGGAAGACCACCAAAAUCCACACCAAAGCCAAGGUCACAUCCAGAGGGAAGGCCCGCGAGGGGCGCAGCCCCACCAGGUGGGCGGCCUUGCCCUCAGACUGCCCGCUGGUGCUGCGGAAGCUCAUGCUCAAGGAAGACACCCGUGCUGGCUGCAAGUGCCUGGUGAAGGCGCCCCUGGUCUCUGACGUGGAGCUGGAGCGCUUCCUGUUGGCGCCCCGAGACCCCAGCCAAGUGCUGGUGUUUGGGAUCAUCUCAAGCCAGAACUACACCAGCACUGGGCAGCUCCAGUGGCUGCUGAACACUCUCUACAACCACCAGCAGCGGGGCCGUGGCUCCCCCUGCAUCCAGUGCCGGUAUGACUCCUACCGCCUGCUGCAGUAUGACCUGGACAGCCCCCUGCAGGAGGACCCUCCCCUGAUGGUGAAGAAGAACUCUGUGGUGCAGGGGAUGAUUCUGAUGUUUGCCGGGGGGAAGCUCAUUUUUGGGGGCCGUGUUUUGAAUGGAUAUGGCCUCAGCAAGCAGAAUCUGCUGAAACAGAUCUUCCGGUCUCAACAGGAUUACAAGAUGGGCUACUUCCUGCCGGAUGACUACAAAUUCAGUAAGCUGAGUCUGGGCCUUGUCCGAGUGGGGCAACCCACUUCUGGAGGAACUGAAGAGGUCAUGCCAAGUGACCCCCACAACUCAGAGCACUCAGCGGGGAAGGCAGGCCCAGGAGGAGCCUGUGGAUGUGUUCCCAACUCUGUCCUGAGCCUGGAGGAUUCUGAAUCAGUCAAGAAAGCCGAGUCAGAAGAUAUCCAAGGAAGCAGCUCCUCAUUGGCCCUGGAAGACUAUGUGGAGAAGGAGUUAUCUCUGGAGGCUGAGAAGACAAGAGAGCCUGAAGUGGAGCUACAUCCUCUCAGCAGGGACAGCAAGAUAACUAGUUGGAAGAAGCAGGCCUCCAAGAAGUAGCGCCAUCCUGGCAGCAGCCAAGUGAGCCAGGCCCCGGCCCGGGGUGCUGGGGCUUCUUGCCAGCCCAGCCCUGCCUCCCCGGUCUCCCACCCUGUCCUCCAAGCUUCUAUAAUAAACCAGCGGGCCUCCAGCAUUGGGGUGAGGCUCUGGGGAAGGACAGA